AUAUUUGUACAGCAACAGCAGGAGCAGCCCACUAGCUAGGCCGUGUGGCCACCCUUUGGCACCCGCACCGGCUCAGACCUGCUCAGGACUCAGCCAGGGCACACAGUUUGUGUUCUUACGUGCAUCCAUCUGUCUGUCUGUGUGCGUCUCUGUGGAGGACUGAGGUUUUCAAGUGAAAGAGAGUGAAGACAUAGUCCAGAGAGGGAAGUGUAAAGCUACAGGUAUGGGCUAACUACUGAAUGGGUGUGCUCCGUGGCUAUCUUUUUAACCUUCUUGCAUGAGGCCUGCUAUGCAGAUAUGAAAAAGUUGCUUUCAGAAAGGUGAUGGCUUCUUUUGUACAUUAUGGGAUAACAUUUGCAAAAUGUGUGUCCCUGGGAAGCUAGAAAUAUUUUCUUGCCCUCUUUUCCAACUCUUUCUCCUUAGCUAUUUUCCAAGGCAGGCUUAUCUCCCACUAAAACUAGCUGCUUCCUAGUUCUUACAGCUGUUGCGGUGAGCGUGUGUAUGUUGGAGGGAGCCGGGAGGAAUACUCUACACCAGACUUGUCCAACCCGCAGCCUGUGGGCUGCAUGUAGCCCAGGACAGCUUUGGAUAUAGCCUAACACAAAUUUAUCAACUUUCUUAAAACAUGAGAUUUUUUUUUUCUUUUUUUUGAGCCGGAGUCUCGCUCUGUCACCCAGGCUGGAGAGCAGUGGCGCGAUCUUGGCUCACUGCAACCCCUCCGCCUCCCGGGUUCAAGCAAUUCUCCUGGCUCAGCCUCCCGAGUAGCUGGGAUUAACAGGCCUGUGCCACCACGCCUGGCUAAUGUUUUGUAUUUUUAGUAGAGACGGGGUUUCAUCGUGUUAGCCAGGAUGGUCUCUAUCUCUUGACCUUGUGAUCCUCCCACCUCGGCCUCCCAAAGUGCUGGGAUUACAGGUGUGAGCCACCGCGCCCAGCCUGCAAAUUUUUUUUUUUUAACUCAUCGGCUAUCAUUAGUAUAUUUUAUUUGUGGCCUAAGACAAUUCCUCUUCCAGUGUGGCACAAGGAAGCCUAAAGAUUGGACACCACUGGAACAGAGAUGAGGACGGAACUUAGUAGAUUCCAUGCACGUACUAAUACCUUCCUUGAACCAGAAUUUGUUCAACAUACUUUUUUUUUUUUUUUUUGGAGACAGAGUUUCACUCUUGUCACCCAGGCUGGAGUGCAGUGGCACGAUCUCAGCUCACUGCAGCCUCUGCCUCCUGGGUUCAGGCAAUUCUCGUGCCUCAGCCUCCUGAGUAGCUGGGAUUACAGGUGCCUGCUACUGUGCCUGGCUAAUUUUUGUAUUUUUGUAUUUUUAGUAGAGACAGGUCUCGAACUCCUGACCUCAGGUGAUCUGCCAGCCUCGGCCUCCCAAAGUACUGGGAUUACAGAUAGGAGCCACUGUGCCCGGCUAACAUACUGAUUUUUUUUUUUUUUUGGAGACAGAGUCUCACUCUGUCAGCCAGGCUGGAGUACAGUGGCACGAUCUCGGCUCACUGCAAGCUCUGCCUCCCAGGUUCACGCCAUUCUCCUGCCUCAGUCUCCUGAGUAGCUGGGACUACAGCUGCCUGCCACCAUGGCCGGCUAAUUUUUUUGUAUUUUUUGUAUUUUUUUUAGUAGAGAGGGGAUUUCACCGUGUUAACCAGGGUGGUCUCGAUCUGACCUCGUGAUCUGCCCAUCUUGGGCUCCUAAAGUGUUGGGAUUCCAGGCAUGAGCCACCGUGCCUGGCCUAACAUACUGAUUUUUAAAUCAGCACUGGAGCUUAAAUAAAGUGUAAACUUACAGUAUAUUGUUACCAACUAAGAAAUGCACUUAAGUUCCAGAACUAGUGUGGGAUCUGAAAGUAUGACUUGAUUGGAAGGGUGGUCACAAUUUGACAGGACUGUUGGGUCAGUGUUACUGACAGAUACUCCAAGGAAGGCUCUGAGGCUAUACUAUUGCUGAGUACACAGCAGUAGUACAGAGCUGAGUACAGAGUCUUUCUGUGAUUAAGGAUAGGGGAGGAAAUGGAAAACUUUUUCGUUUUCAAAAUGGUGAUGUUUUUGUCAUAUCCUUUCAGUAUACUGUAUGUGGUAAUUUUACAGGCAAGGCAACUUGUACACAACAAAUUAUUAAAUGUAGUGCUUUUUUGGUACAGUGAUUUUAGAUUUGAAAUGGAAAUUUUUUUUUUUUUUUUUUUGGUGACAGAGUCUCACUCUAUCGCCCAGGCUGGAGUGCAAUGGCAUGGUGUCGGCUUACUGCAACCUCCGCCUCCUGGGUUCAAGCGAUUCUCCUGUCUCAGCCUCCCAAGUAGCUGGGACUACAGGCACCUGCCACCACAUCCGGCUAAUUUUUGUAUUUUUAGUAGAGAUGGGGUUUCACCAUGUUGAUCAAACUGGUCUAGAACUCCUGACCUUAGGUGAUCUGCUCACCUCGGCCUUCCAAAGUGCUGGGAUUAGAGGCGGUGAGCCACCGCGCCCAGCCUGAAAUGGAGGUUUUUUAUGUUUUAUUUAUUUUGUUUUGUAAGGCAGGGUCUCACGCUGUUGCCCAUGCUGGAGUGUAGUGGUGCGAUCAAGUAUCACUGCAGCGUUGACCUUCCUGGGGUCAGGUGAUCCUCCCACUUCAGCCUCACAAGUAGCUGGGACUACAGGUGGGCACCAUCAUGCCUCACUAUUUUUUGUAUUUUUUUGUAGAGAUGGCGCCAUGUUGCCCAGGCUAGUCUUGCCUGAGCUCAAAUGAUGCUCCUGCCUUGGCCUCCCAAAGUGCUGGGAUUACAGGCGUUUCCCACUGUGCCCAGCCAGAAAAAUUCUUUUUACAAUAUUUCUAUUUCUUCUUUAACCCCCCUCCCCCACCAUUCAGAAAUUUUUACAUUGUCUAGAUUCUUAUGGAAAACUUAUUUUGUUGUUUUGUUUUUUGUUUGUUUGUUUUGAGACAGGGUCUUAUUCUGUUGCCCAGGCUAGAGUGCAGUGGCUCAAUCUUGGUUCACUGCAGCCUUGACCUCCUGGGCCCAGUCACUCCUCCUGCCUCAGCCUCCUGAGUAGCUGAGACUACAGUAUGCAUCACCACACUCAGCUAAUGUUUUGUAUUUUUUUGUAGAGAUAGGUCUCUCUUUGUUGGUCAGACUAGUCUCAAACUCCUGGGCUUGAACAGUCUGCCCACCUUGGCCUCCCAAAGUGUUGGGAAUAUAGGCGUGAAGCCUGUGUUCUUGCCCCGUAAAUUAUUCUUAACCGUCACAUUUUGUAACAAUAACAGAAAUCUUCCACAAAGUGAAAUGCCACAGAGAUAAUUACCAGUUUGUGUCACCAUAUUUUACCUAUGCAAGCAAGGUACUUGGCUGGGAGCUCAGGAGACCCAGUAGUUAUAUUAGAAAUACUCGAUUUUAGAAAUGAAAUUUAGGUCCAAAAAGGUACUGUGCAAAAAUUUAAGUUACUGUAGUUGGUUAUUUUCAAGUAUCAAUUGCUUACUUUUUUUCUCUCUUAUGAAACUUGGGGGUAAAAUACCCAGUCCACUUAGCAGCAAUCUGAGGUUAUAACCAUUCCCUAGAUUUUUGCAAUUUGAAUUCCCUCAUAUAGAUUGAUGGUGAUUUUUAAUGACAUUGAUUCCCUUUUCAGUAGUAGCUUCUAAUCUCCUCUGUGCUUAUAUAACUAGACUUUACUUUAUUGCCCUUUCAAACAUACUUAGAUUUAUUGGGGUGGAAGUGUAAAAUCUGUUCACCUGUUGUAGAACUCCCUGGUUAUAUCUAUCAAGGUAGACAUUUGCAUAUGCCAACUAGGCUUUUUUGCUUAACUGUGCUUUUGUUUGCUUUUUCAUCCUUUUGGCAAAACAUACUGUGAUUGCUAGCCUUUCUCUUUUCUAAUCCAGUUUUACAUCUUCCUGUUAAGUUUAUACUAUUCCUAUAUCCUAAAUGCAAUGAAUGCUGUUCUUUUGAGUGUUUUUCUUACCUAUAUUGAUCACUUUUAAUGAUUUGGGUUCUUAAUGUUACAGCAGGCUGACUACUCCUACCUUCACUUAAUCAGGCUUUGAAUUGUUGCUCUUUUAAAAAGUAGAGAAUAUUCAAGGCAGAGAAUACUGAGACAGACGGACAACCAGGGAGAGAAGAGGAAACCAUGAAAGUACAUUCAGAGUGAAAGGAACAGGCUGAACAUAACUUCUUUUUUUCAAAGUUCCCUGUGUUGUGAACUGAGCUUGGGUGAAGUGAAAUCUUUGAGGAAGCUAAAGCUGUGUGUAUUUGUGGAUCAGACAAGUGCAGCAAGUUAAUAUCAUUGGCUUCUGAAGGGGAGAGUGAGGUGAUGGCUGCGUUUAAGUUGGAUUUCCUUCCAGAAAUGAUGGUGGAUCAUUGCUCUUUGAAUUCCAGUCCCGUCUCAAAGAAAAUGAACGGCACCCUGGACCACCCAGACCAACCAGAUCUUGAUGCUAUCAAGAUGUUUGUGGGCCAGGUUCCAAGGACCUGGUCUGAAAAGGACUUGCGGGAACUCUUCGAACAGUAUGGUGCUGUGUAUGAAAUCAACGUCCUAAGGGAUAGGAGCCAAAACCCGCCUCAGAGCAAAGGGUGCUGUUUUGUUACAUUUUACACCCGUAAAGCUGCAUUAGAAGCUCAGAAUGCUCUUCACAACAUGAAAGUCCUCCCAGGGAUGCAUCACCCUAUACAGAUGAAACCUGCUGACAGUGAGAAGAACAAUGCAGUGGAAGACAGGAAGCUGUUUAUUGGUAUGAUUUCCAAGAAGUGCACUGAAAAUGACAUCCGAGUCAUGUUCUCUUCGUUUGGACAGAUUGAAGAAUGCCGGAUAUUGCGGGGACCUGAUGGCCUGAGCCGAGGUUGUGCAUUUGUGACUUUUACAACAAGAGCCAUGGCACAGACGGCUAUCAAGGCAAUGCACCAAGCACAGACCAUGGAGGGUUGCUCAUCACCCAUGGUGGUAAAAUUUGCUGAUACACAGAAGGACAAAGAACAGAAGAGAAUGGCCCAGCAGCUCCAGCAGCAGAUGCAGCAAAUCAGCGCAGCAUCUGUGUGGGGAAACCUUGCUGGUCUAAAUACUCUUGGACCCCAGUAUUUAGCACUUUAUUUGCAGCUCCUUCAGCAGACUGCCUCCUCUGGGAACCUCAACACCCUGAGCAGCCUCCACCCAAUGGGAGGGUUGAAUGCAAUGCAGUUACAGAAUUUGGCUGCACUAGCUGCUGCAGCUAGUGCAGCUCAGAACACACCAAGUGGUACCAAUGCUCUCACUACAUCCAGCAGUCCCCUCAGCGUGCUCACUAGUUCAGCAGGGUCCUCACCUAGCUCUAGCAGCAGUAAUUCUGUCAACCCCAUAGCCUCACUUGGAGCCCUGCAGACAUUAGCUGGAGCAACGGCUGGCCUCAAUGUUGGCUCUUUGGCAGGAAUGGCUGCUUUAAAUGGUGGCCUGGGCAGCAGUGGCCUUUCCAAUGGCACCGGGAGCACCAUGGAGGCCCUCACUCAGGCCUACUCGGGUAUCCAGCAAUAUGCUGCUGCUGCGCUCCCCACUCUGUACAACCAGAAUCUUCUGACACAGCAGAGUAUUGGUGCUGCUGGAAGCCAGAAGGAAGGUCCAGAGGGAGCCAACCUGUUCAUCUACCACCUGCCCCAGGAGUUUGGUGAUCAGGACCUGCUGCAGAUGUUUAUGCCCUUUGGGAAUGUCGUGUCUGCCAAGGUUUUCAUAGACAAGCAGACAAACCUGAGCAAGUGUUUUGGUUUUGUAAGUUACGACAAUCCUGUUUCGGCCCAAGCUGCCAUCCAGUCCAUGAACGGCUUUCAGAUUGGCAUGAAGCGGCUUAAAGUGCAGCUCAAACGUUCGAAGAAUGACAGCAAGCCCUACUGAGCGUGCUCCCCUCUGAGACUGGAGUGAGAGGGUCUUCUGGUAAGUGGGGGAGGAGCACCCUUAAUGAUUCGAAGCCCUGAGGCUGUGUGUUGACAGCCCUGGACCCUGAUCCCUGCCACUCUCGCAGGCACAGCUUGCCCUGAAGACUCGGCUACUGCCUUCUGUGGGAGUUUCGCUUCGUACAGAGGACAAGUUUGUGCUUUGGUUUCCAGUGUUUUACUUUGGAGUUUAGGUGCCAUAUCCUGAGGUUUUUUUUGUUUUUGUUUUUGUUUCUCCUUUAUUUAAAGUUUGCUGUGUUUGUAACCAGUGUGUGUUGAGAAGGACCAACACCAAACCACCCUGGGGAAGGGGGACAGGGAAACAUUUAACACAGACGAUGAUCAGGAUUUGCCCCAAACCACCCCAAGAGAGAGGACUGAGUGGAACAAAAAAGUGACCCCCAGAACCUCUCUUAGUGUGAGGGUGGGUAGAAUGAGAACUGACACCUGGGAGCUGUGGGGAGCAGAGCGGCUUUGGGGAAGAGUGGAGUGACUAGACACCUAAUGCCCUGGCAGCUGGAGACUCAAACUCCUGUACAGCUACCUUCUGGGAAAUAGUUUUUGACACCUAUUUUUCAGAUUCUUGUCCGGAAUUUCUGCUGCUCUUUUCAAAAAAGGGCAUUAACAAUUCUCUGGAAAUAAAGCACCUGUUAGCCUGACAUAUGCAAAAAGCAGGGCGGCAUCACCCAUUACGAGCUCCCCCAGCCAGCAGUCAGUAUUGGAUUGGCCUUGCCUGGCUGGUGGCAGUUUGGGAGAAACAGCCAAAGAGGUUAGUUUAUUUCAACACCAAAUUAGACCAUGGCCCAUUUCCAACGGGUCUCUUUAAAGGCCUCUAUGGAAUACAUUGCCUGGUUUCCUUCUUUGCAGUUCACCACAGCAAGGAAUGUCACCUCCAUCCCAAGCCACCAUUUUCUCAUGAAGGCAAAUCCAAGAAGGGCUUGCAGUUCUUGCUGAAGGGGGUACCAUUUGUGGGCAGAGUGAUCAAUACCAUCUAGUUGGGGGAGGAGGAGCUUAUUUCUUGGUGUACUUGAAUCAGAAGGUCCCUGCAAGCCAGUAUGCUUCAUUUGCCAGUGGCCAGAAAUUCUCCCUUGCCUCCUUGAUUGAGGUGUCCCAGAUGUAGUAUUCCCACAGGGGUCUGGCAGGCCCCUCCUGUAACCACUCCAGUCACAUUUUCUGCUCUUGAGGCAGAGGUGACAUCAGGACGUUUACAGCCUCCACAUGAAUUGAGUGUUCAUUUACCUCAGUAUUACCGUGUUCAUUUUUGUCCUCGUGCUACAGUUAGCUCCCUGCCGCCUCUUGCAGGUCUUACUUCAGCUCUUGCCUGUGACCCACACAGCUUCUGGGCUCUGCCUCUGCUCUAAGAAGUGCUGUGGGGGUAGAGAACCAGGAAGGACAUGCUGUUGGGAAUGUACACCUGGGCAGAGGUGGCCCUGUUAAGAUGUGACUGUAGCCACAGCCAGGGAUGGGAUCCCUGGGUCUCUGGAAUCUGAAACCUCAACAAAUACCAGUCUUGACCCCUAGCAGCAGAGAUAAGAAUAAAGGGGUUGGUUUGCUAUUAAGUCAGAUGGGGGCUCUCUCCUUGUCAUGCUGUCCCUGUGGGUAACAGACAGGGAUUGACCAUCUUACUGUUGUACAGGUAGCUGGUGGUGUUGGAUUAUCCCAUUGAAGCUGGGACAGCUGUUCCUUUCUCAUAGUGAUAACUUGGGUCUGUUGUCCUCUAAGGAACGUGAAACAUACACUUCUUAAGCUGAACCACGUAAACUUGAAAUUCUGCGCACUGGGAGAAAUGUGUCCUGUGUUUCAAAGGAUAAAACUGUUCUAAAGGCUUCCAGGGUCAUGAUGGGAUUUUUUAAAUAAAUGCAAAAAAUAAAAAUAAAAAAGAAAAAAGAAAACAAAAAAAAAAAAGAAAAAAAUGCUAGGUUGGGGAGGCGCUGUUCUGAAUCCCAACCGGCUGGAACCAAGAAUGUCGUUUCUAUUUUUAUAGAAGUUUUAUACAGCUCCGGGGUGGAGAAUAUUUAUUACCUAAAUUAUAUCUCUGGAAAAGGCCAGGAUUUUGUAGAAUCCAGAAUGUGAUUGUUAUACACACAGGGUGCUGUGUAUGAUUGAAACUACUGACUUUCUGUGGCCCGUUUGCAGCCCAGCUAACCUGCCCAAGGGGAAGGUGUUAAUGCUGUGAAUUGGCAGAGGAGAGAGCUGUGCUCCAUAGGGUGCUGCCGGUGCUGUGCUCCCUAGCCUUCUGUUCUGUCUUCCUCCUUAGCCAGAACGCCACUCCCUUCCCACAUCCCCUUCUUCUCUCCGCCUUCCCCCAUCUCACCAUUAUUUGUCCAUGGAUUUGUCCUGGGCUCUGGGACCUUAUGAAACCCCUUUCCUAAUGACAUAAGAGGCCAAGGUGCAAUCCACCCACCUUUGAUACCAGACCCUGAGGGCUUCAUACCUGCUGAUGGGUUUUCUUUUCUAAAAGGAAUGCUCGCCCCAGCAGGGUCCUGGGCUGCUUGAGCAGCCAGCUGGUGAGACCAUGCACUUCUCUGUUCUCUCCUCCCCCUGCCCAGUGAGUUAGCACAGCAGUAGCACUGCCCUUGAGCACAGUUCUUUCCCCAGGCCAAAGAUGGUUUUGUGAAGAAGCUGCUCCCCUACAAGUCUCACGUGUGAAAGGGCUCAGCUCAGAGUGGAGACUCGCUGUCAAGUCUUAAGCAAUCCUUUUCUGUUGUGUGAAGGUUUCACUUACAAUGUGUUUUCUGCUGUAGUUUUGUUUCUUACUUGGGUUACAUCAUGAAAUUGAUUUGCCUUGAAUGCAGCCAGACCACUGUCUCCUGGGUUCCCCUUGAGUGGCCAGGGCCUGGAUGGAAGCUAAGAGCUUGGAUUUCUGGGAACAAAGGGCCAUCCCCAUAAGAUUGAGCAGAAAUUCUGGUCCUCUUCCCUGAAAAAUUUUCCCCACCCCAGCCAGCAUCUUCUGCUUCCCCUUGGGUUGUGACCAGGGAGUGGGGAGAGAGGCUGAGGCUCUGCUCCCCUGGAGACCUUCUCUUAGGAGUUGGGUGCUUCAUGGAAAAUCCAAGCCUUAGGUUCCCUUCUGUCUCUGGCAAUUAGAUGUGUUCUUGGUGUCCUCCAUGUCCUUUUUGACUUUUCCCUGUGUCCAUUGUUAGCAUGUGCAAAAGUUCCCUGUCAUUACCCAACCCCUGCCCGCCCACCUCAUUUCAGGGCUGUACACACAGUGAGUGUUCCUGUUCUCUCUCUCUUUGUUUGGAUGUAUUGCUCUGUGUAACUCAGUGGGUCUCCCUCUUUCUGGUUUGUUUUUUUUUCUAGAUUCCUGCCGUUUGUUCAUCGUUGUGCCUAAAGCAUGUCGAUGUGGCGUCAAGUACAUCGUCCAAAUCCCUGUCUCUUCAGCUUCUCUGAUGCUUGAACUCUCACCUUUGACCUUGUGUUGACCUUUGAUGCUGAUGUGUAUUUUUAUUAUGUUUGUUUCUUUCUUCGUUUUUUUUUCUUUUUUUCUUUCCUUUUUUUUUCCUUUUGUGCUGCCAAAUUGGUUUUGCUAGAACGACUGCUGAAGGGGAAAUAUUUAAACUUGCAUUUGAAUAUAAAAAAAAUCUAUUUUUCUAGAACUUCAUAAGAUAACCACUUGAUUUUGUGAUUCCAAUUCUUUGUAAUUGUCUUCAGAGCAGCCCUACUAGCACAUACCGCGUGGUGUUUGUAUUUCUGUGAACACACAGCCAGUCCGUUUCUAGGCUUUGUUUCUCUGUGUGCUUAGUUUUAAAGACAACUUUGAAGUAAACAAUGAAAUAAAAGAUGUCACUAAAACCUCUGAGGCUCCUGAGCACAUUUUGCUGAUACAGUCUGUGGGGCUUGAGGAGACCGCAUGUAUUGUUCUUUCUUUUGUUUUUCUUCUGAGUUCUCAACUGCGGAGAGCACCUGAACCCCCUUUCCUUUUUGACCGCAGGCUGCACUUUGGGCCCCAGCCAGCCCUUUUUCUUUUUCUUUUUCUUUUGUGGUUCUUCCCUGGAGCGACUCUGGGGAGUCCUGGAUAUCCCGCCUGCCCCUUCCCCUCAGCCCCAUGCUUGUUCCAACAGUCUCCACAGCAAAAUGUGAUGCUUUGAUUUUUUUGUUGUUGUUUUUGUUUUUGUAUUGUUUUUGUGUUUUUGUUUUGAAUUUUUUCCUUUCCUACUAAGAUUAUGCCCAGAAAAAAGUUUUGCAUGUUUCCUGCUGUUUCUUCACACCUUCGUAUAUAUCACCUUCACCUCUCUGUUUUCUAUAGUUUGUGCAAAAACUGAUCGAUUUAAAAGGGUUUCAAAGAAGCUGUUUUAAAUUGUUGUAGGGUUGAUUAUUUUUUUCAAGAUUGUAUUGUUUAAUUUUGAAGUGGCAACUUUCUCCUCUAUUGCCCUUAGAGCGUUUGCCUGUGCACUUAGACUGUCACUUCGUGUGGCCUCCAGGUCUUACCGGGGCUUCCGGGAGGCUGGCUGCUUUGCUCAGAGAGGGUGGGAAGGGGGCCUGGAGAGACACGAGAAGCAGAGGUAGAGCCUAGAAGGUGGCAGCAGGUGGGUAAGAGGCUUAUUUAGCACAUUAGGGGCAGUGAGCACCUGGAGGAAGGAGGGCGCUCCCAAUCACCCGUAGGAGGCCAUCUGCACACCAAGCGGCAAUUCACCUGCUGGCGCUUUUCCUAGGUGACAAGCACAAUACUACAGUCUUCACACUGUUUACAGCCCUGGGCACCAGCCACCCGGCACUGGCUCUUCAUCACAGCUCUGCUCUUGCUUAGCUAGUGGGGUGGGGGAAAGGGCAGGGAUUUGUUUUUUUAAUUGGGUGGAGAGCCAAACAGCUACUGUCCCUGGGUGCCAAGCAAGCCAGUUUUUUGGUUCCCUGAGGGAAACUGACCCUCCUCUCUUGUGGCACCAUCCAGCCUCAGGGUCUUGGAGACUUGAGUAAGAAUGUGAGUGGAGGGGGAGAGGUGAGGAGAGGAGCACAGGGUGGAUCUGUGGAGGGAAGAGGUUACAGGGGGAGGAGCUGAUGAUAGAUCCCACCCAGACUUAAGCUGCUGGUGGGUGGGUGAGCUGGGAAGUAGGACUGUCCAGGGAAGGGUGGAGAGAUGUAGCUAGGGGCUGGGGAGGGGGAGGUGGAAGCGCUAUUGAGCAUCCUCCACACCAAGGUUGAUGAAGGAAGGGAUCCCAGCAGGGUUUCUGCUCUGGGGCUGGCAGGUUGCCUGGUAUUAUGCCCAAGGCCGCUCUGCCUGGGGGAAAGGGCAGCCAGGCAGAGGCCCAGUGUCUGGUAGGCUGCUGAAUUUCCUGGAAGGGGUGAUUGGAUGGAAAGAGGCCAGAAACCCCAGCCUGAGAGACUGCUGUGCACCCCACAGUCUGACUGCACAGAGCCGCCUCUGUUGGCAGGAGGCACUGAGGCUCCCCUUCCUGUGUAUUGAGAAGCAGUGUUUGCCAAUAUAUUUUGCUUUCAAUUCCAAGAGGAGCUCUGGGAAAACCUGUGGAUAAAACCAAAUGCCAAAUGUUGGACGUUGUUUCCUUUUCCUUUUCUCUCUCUGAUUGUUUUAAUUGUUCUGUGGUGGUUUUAAUGGAUUUGAGACCCUGGAGCGGCAGCUGCCUUUCUGAUUUCCAGCUGCUUUUUGUGAAUAAUUUAAAAAGAAAAAAAAAAAGAAACUUUACAUUUUGGAGACAAACCUGUGUGAGUUUUUUAUUGGUACAAACGUUGUAUUUAACACUAGGGGUUUUGUACAGUUUUUUGCCUUUUCUACUAGAAAACAAUGUAAAGUGAUUUCACAAUGUGAAGAGAAAAAAAAAUUGCCACUAUGACCAAACGCACAGUCUGUUCUGCAGCAACAACGGGAUUCAAUCAACUCAGUCGUGAUUCAGCCGUAGAAAUGCUUUUCCUUUAUCUUGUUUGAGCUUUUCCUUUCUUUCCUGUUUUGAUUUGCAAAAGAAAAUGUCUUUUUUGUGUGAACUUGUGUUGUACUCUGUAGAAAAUUAUGGAUUUUACUUUAAUGGUUUAAAAAAAGGCAAGGAGAGCCCUCGUCGCUUUUCUUACCUAAUCACAGAGUUUGUGUAGUGAAUUUAAAAAGAAAAAAAAAUUGUUAUAAGUUUGGAGCAAGGGAGUAUGUGUUUCAAAGGAAUCUCCUUCCUUUUUUUGUGUGUUUUUCCUUUUGUCCCAAUGGGGAACCUAAAUCUGUUUUAAUUGCACAGACACAUGGACAAAAAGUCAUUUUGUAUCUGCCAAGUGUGGUACCUUCCUUUGUUUAUUUGCUAUUAAACUGUUUGAGAAGAA